CCCAGAGCCCGGAUUCGUGAAGCAGUUGAGUGCUGCAGCGGCAGUCGUCGCCCCUGCCGCCGCUGCCACCGAAGGAAGCAUCCCAGACACCGGGAAGAUGGAAGAUGGUACCCCAAAGCAUAUCAUCCAGAUGACAGGAUUUAAGAUGGAAGAAAAAGAAGCGCUAGUCAAAUUACUUUUAAAACUAGAUUGCACUUUUAUUAAGAGUGAGAAAUACAAAAAUUGUACACAUCUUAUAGCUGAACGCCUAUGUAAGAGUGAAAAAUUUUUAGCAGCUUGUGCGGCAGGAAAGUGGAUACUAACCAAGGACUAUAUAAUUCAUAGUGCCAAAAGUGGCAGAUGGCUUGAUGAAACAACUUAUGAAUGGGGAUAUAAAAUUGAAAAAGAUUCCCGUUAUUCACCUCAAAUGCAAUCUGCACCUAAAAGAUGGCGUGAAGAACUGAAACGCACUGGUGCUCCAGGAGCCUUCCACAGAUGGAAAGUUGUCCUCCUUGUUAGAACUGAUAAGCGAAGUGAUUCUCUUAUAAGAGUUUUGGAGGCUGGAAAGGCAAAUGUUAUUUUACCAAAAAGUUCACCAAGUGGAAUAACUCAUGUGAUUGCCAGUAAUGCAAGAAUUAAAGCUGAGAAAGAAAAAGAUAACUUUAAGGCUCCAUUUUAUCCAAUUCAGUAUCUAGGGGAUUUUCUUUUAGAGAAAGAAAUUCAGAAUGAUGAAGAUUCCCAAACCAAUUCUGUUUGGACUGAACAUAGCAAUGAAGAAACAAACAAAGAUUUCAGGAAAGAUGCAGGAUUUCUUGAAAUGAAAGGUGCCUUAAGAGAGACCAUGUAUAGAACCCAGAAAGAAAUGCAAAAUCAUGAAGAUGUUAAUGUUGGUUCUAUUUUGAUUCAACAUCACAAAAAAGAAAAAUUCAGUGGUUCCAGUAAAGAUUUGAAAUUUGUUAAAAUGAGAAAUACCUUUGGAAGCCAUACAUAUGAAAAUCAGAAGGAAAUUAAGAAAAAAGAUGAAGAUAUUCAGAGGAGUUAUACUUUGAGGAGAAAACGCAAGAAAGGAAAAGAAAGCAAUUGCAAGAAAGGCGUUGAACAUGAAAAAAUAAAAAGUACCUUAAGAAGGCACAUAUAUAAUAGAGAUCAGAAAGAAAUGAAGAAUUCUAUUUUUGCUGAAUAUGCCAAAGAAUCAAAAGCCAUGGCUAUUAAGACAGAUGUGGAUGUUGUUGAAAUAAAAAAUACCUUAAGGAAGCACAUAUAUAGAGCUCAGGCUGUCAGAUACAACUGCAUUAGAAUAGAUAAACAACCAGUGUACAACGUAGAGGUUAAAAAUGCUGAAUUUCCCAGAGGUGUAUUAAAUUUAAUUGAAAGCCUCAUAGAAGGACAUUUUUUUAAAGAAGCAAUUGAGGAACUUUCCACUUUGCAGGCACAUUAUAUCCCUCCUGUAUGCGUUCUUCAUGCCCUUCUAGAGAACGUUCUACAGGAUAACAUAGAUACAUUUUCUGGUCGAUACUUUCAUAUAUUGUCAGCUCUUCUUCACCUGCAUCCUCCUUGGAAGUCUCCAGCCAUGUCGAGAUAUUAUUUAGAGUUGUUUCAGUGUCCAACUUGUAUGAAAGGAGCAUGGUCUUUAGUAGAAGUCCUUAUCAGGUCUUGCCUUUUCAAUGAAAGCUUUUGUCAUCAAAUUUCAGAAAAUAUUGGCUCCAAGGUGCUCCACCUGACGCUACUCAAAUUUUUCUUUAAUUUAAUUGAAAGUGAAGUACAACAUCUGAGUCAAAAGUUGUAUGACUGGUCAGAUUCUCAGAAUCUGAAAAUAACAGGAAAGGCAAUGCUUCUUGAAAUUUUUUGGUCAGGAAGUGAAACCUCUGGGCUUUUGACCAAACCAGUAAAUAUGCUUUUGGAAUGGACUAUAUAUUCUCACAAGGAAAAAUUCAAGUCUAAUGAUGUCUUCAAACAUGAACUAGCUUACUUAUUGGCUGGAAUUCUUGGAGCAGCAAUAGAUUAUUGGAUUUUCCUUGGUCUUAAGAUGGGUAGAAAUGUGAUGCGACACAUGUCUGAUGACUUAGGAAGUUAUGUUUCUCUUUCGUGUGAUGACUUUUCUUCACAGGAAUUAGAGAUUUUCAUUUGCUCCUUUUCCUCCUCCUGGCUUCAAAUGUUUGUUGCAGAGGCAGUCUUUAAAAAGUUGUGUCUACAGAGCUCUGGCAGUGUUUCUUCUGAGCCACUCUCUCUUCAGAAAAUGGUAUAUUCCUAUUUACCAGCCUUGGGGAAAACUGGUGUGCUUGGGUCUGGAAAGAUUCAGGUGUCAAAGAAAAUAGGACAGCGGCCUUGUUUUGACUCUCAGAGAACCUUACUAAUGCUGAAUGGUACUAAACAAAAACAAGUCGAAGGGCUGCCAGAGUUACUAGACCUGAACCUUGCUAAAUGUUCCUCAUCAUUAAAAAAAUUGAAAAAGAAGUCAGAAGGAGAAUUGUCAUGUUCCAAGGAGAAUUGCCCCUCUGUAGUUAAAAAGAUGAAUUUUCACAAGACUAAUCUAAAAGGAGAAACAGCCCUGCAUAGAGCUUGCAUAAAUAACCAAGUGGAGAAAUUGAUUCUUCUUCUCUCUUUGCCAGGAAUAGACAUCAAUGUUAAAGACAAUGCUGGCUGGACGCCUUUGCAUGAAGCCUGUAACUAUGGCAACACAGUGUGUGUCCAGGAAAUUUUGCAACGUUGUCCAGAGGUAGAUCUGCUCACUCAAGUGGACGGGGUGACUCCUUUGCAUGAUGCACUGUCAAACGGACAUGUAGAAAUUGGCAAGCUGCUACUACAGCAUGGGGGCCCAGUGCUUUUACAACAGAGGAAUGCUAAGGGAGAAUUGCCCUUGGAUUAUGUGGUUUCACCUCAAAUCAAAGAAGAACUGUUUGCUAUUACAAAAAUAGAAGAUACAGUGGAGAACUUUCAUGCACAAGCAGAGAAACAUUUUCAUUACCAGCAACUUGAAUUUGGCUCCUUUUUACUUAGUAGGAUGUUGCUAAAUUUUUGUUCAAUUUUUGAUUUAUCUUCAGAGUUCAUUUUAGCUUCCAAAGGGUUAACUCAUCUAAAUGAACUGCUUAUGGCUUGUAAAAGUCAUAAAGAAACCACCAGUGUUCAUACUGACUGGUUACUGGAUCUUUAUGCUGGAAAUAUAAAGACAUUGCAGAAACUCCCACACAUUCUUAAGGAACUGCCUGAGAAUUUGAAAGUGUGUCCUGGGGUACACACUGAGGCCUUGAUGAUAACAUUGGAAAUGAUGUGUCGGUCAGUCAUGGAGUUUUCAUGAUGAUGCUAGAAAGUAUGGAUUGACUUUCUAAAUCUGUUCAGUUUGCAUUGGUACUUACUGUGGACUUCAUAGCUUACUGACAGAUAGUAAUUUGAUUUAUUUAUUGACAGACUUUGCAGCCUUGCUAAAUUUUAAAAGCAUUUUUAAAAAAACUUCUACAAAACUCUAGUAUGGGCUUCUGACUUUUUCCAGGGUGUAGAAUUUGACUCAAAAGUAAAAAUAAUUUUGUUUUAGUAUAUUCUACUUUCAUUAAUGUUUUUUUGUUCUGAAAGUGAUAUUAUAUUGUACAUGUAAAAUUAAUUUAAAUAUUUUUUCAAAUAAAAAUGUAAUGUCCUGUAUUCUAGAUGUUCUAGGUCUUAGAAUCAUGGCAAGCAUAUUCAUACAAAUGCGUACCUAUAAACUUGUAGCUCCUGACUCUUAGGGAUGGAUUUUGAGGAAAAAACAAGACUAAACAAAAACAUGUAGCUCCCUAUUUCUUCUCUCUAGGUUGUUGGACUGAAAUAUGCAUUUUAGCUUUGUGUGUUUCUAAAAUAAACAUUUCUAAAAUUUACAGUAAUAAUUAAUAUUCUUUUGGUUUUUAAAUGCAGCAAAUAUGCAGAGUCUGACAGUUCAAUUCCUUGAUCUGUUUUAUUUUAGCAAUUCAUAUACAAAAUGUAUCUGUCGCUGCCCUAUGUAACCCAGUAUUCUGUACCUGAAAACAUUCUGCUGCAUAGGUUUAUGAGUUUAAUAUUAAGAUAUUGAGUGGCAUCUAAGUAAUAGAUUUGAGAUUAUUUAAGAUCUUAAUAUAUAGUAUGAAUUUACUGAGUAGUAAUGUUUUAAUUUGCAGUUUUUCCUUAUAGCAGUUUGUAGUAAAACUAAAAGAAAGGGUGUGGAUAAUAACCACUUUUGAGAUUGGAGUUUCUUCACUACUGGGAGUAAGUUACAUUAUGAUACAGGUGGAAAAUAAACACUUCCAUUUAGCUUUUAUGUAAUUCAAGUGAUGACCUUAGCAGUUAAUCUGCUAAAGCAAUACACUUCAGUUUUAUUUUGGAAAUAGAUAUUUUAACAAGAUACAAAUGCUCAGUAUCAUAUUACUGGGUUUGUAAUCUAAAUUGAAAACUGCUAUAUCAGUAUGAAAAAAUAUUUUAAAUAAGUACUUUUUCCACACAUACUCAGGAAAUACUAGUUUCUAUUUAGCCUUCAAAUUUGGCAUCAUACAAAUCUCUUUAUUAUUAAUCUGCCAAAGUAUCAGACAAAAAAUGAUAUAGUGAAGACUAUCUAAGAAGAGUUUAAAUGCUUAUAGAGAGUAAAGUGCUUCUCCAGAUGAUGAAUAAGAACGUUUUUUAUUCCAAUGAGUACCUCUUUACUUCACUUGUAAAGGUGUCUGGGAUAGUGUUUGCUUGGUAAACUAAUAUAAACUUGUAAACAUAGGCUUUGACAUCAUACACAUUUUCAAAUCCUUGUCUAGUUUCUUAAUAACUAAAUUGCAAGGCAAAUUCUUUUCUGAGCUUUGGCUUUCCUACAUGUCAAAUAGAAAUCACACCAGGUAUCUUUGUCAUGAUAGAAUUGUUAGCAUAUCACAUCAUAUGACACUUAAUAAAUAUUAUUUCCUUUCUAAUUCUUACCUCCUCUUUUGAUUAUAAUGAAUCAUUUAGACAAAAGGCAAUAUAGUAAUUGUUUAAGUUGGUAGUAAUUCUAAGGUAAUUAAGGAAUCAACAUCAUGAGUUAGGGUUUUAUACUGUUAGUACAAAGUAGUUUUCCAAAUUAGAUGUUCAUAACGUAUAUUUGUUUAAUUGCAAUUAGCAUUAAUAUUUCAUAAUUGACUGCUCUGUCUGCCAACUUCUACAAGCAGUGAUGACAUGAAGUGUGAAACAGAUGUCACUGAGGUCUCUGCCUUUAAGAAGUUUUACACUUCUUCGAAAGUCCAACGUGGCAAACAUAGGUUACUGUGUUCUGUGCCCUGGCUAACAAUACCAGUAUAUGAGUAUGAAUCUAAAUGUUCAGGAAAAGGCUUCAUUCCCAAAAUUACUUCUUAUACUUUAUUUUAGAAAACAUAAUAAUAAUUGCCUUGAAUAAUUGCCCAAAUCUAUCUUGGAGGUAUAGGAAGAAGAAAUUCUCAAUAAGUAAAGUAUAAUUCAUAGUCUUAGUCCUAGAUUUUCAAUGGCAGACUUUUCAAAGUUGCAUCUGAAGACAAGGUUGAGAAAUGCUAUUCUUCACUGUAUUUUGCCAGAUGUGAUAUCAUAGUUCUAUGGAAUCAUAUUUUUUAAAUUUCUGUAAGAGACCUUAUUACAAUGUAAAUAAAGCUGGAGAGGAGAUUUCUGAGCAGUUAA